AGACCGCCGCUGCUGUCUGCGGGGUCUGGUGCCGGGGCCUGAGUCUCUGCUGGCUAAGCCGCCGCCUCAGCCGCCUCAGUCGCCUCAAUCUCGCCUUCCGCCCUCGCUCUCCCUCCGCGCCACCAGACCCCGUAGCCCCGCGCGCCCCCAGCCCUUUAAGCCAGAUGAUGAACUUCCUGCGGCGCCGGCUGUCGGACAGCAGCUUCAUCGCCAACCUGCCCAACGGCUACAUGACCGACCUGCAGCGGCCCGAGCCCCAGCAGCCGCCGCCGCCGCCGCCCCCCGGUCCGGGCGCCGCCUCGGCCUCGGCGGCGCCCCCGACCGCCUCGCCGGGCCCGGAGCGGAGGCCGCCGCCCGCCUCGGCGCCCGCGCCGCAGCCCGCGCCGACGCCGUCGGUGGGCAGCAGCUUCUUCAGCUCGCUGUCCCAAGCCGUGAAGCAGACGGCCGCCUCGGCUGGCCUGGUGGACGCGCCCGCUCCCGCGCCCGCAGCCGCCAGGAAGGCCAAGGUGCUGCUGGUGGUCGACGAGCCGCACGCCGACUGGGCCAAGUGCUUUCGGGGCAAAAAAGUCCUUGGAGAUUAUGAUAUCAAGGUGGAACAGGCAGAAUUUUCAGAGCUCAACCUGGUGGCCCAUGCAGAUGGCACCUAUGCUGUGGAUAUGCAGGUUCUCCGGAAUGGCACAAAGGUUGUCCGGUCCUUCCGGCCAGACUUCGUGCUCAUCCGGCAGCAUGCAUUUGGCAUGGCGGAGAAUGAGGACUUCCGCCACCUGAUCAUUGGUAUGCAGUAUGCAGGCCUCCCCAGCAUCAACUCACUGGAAUCCAUAUACAACUUCUGUGACAAGCCAUGGGUGUUUGCCCAGCUGGUCGCUAUCUAUAAGACACUGGGAGGAGAAAAGUUCCCUCUCAUUGAACAGACAUACUACCCCAACCACAAAGAGAUGCUGACACUGCCCACGUUCCCUGUGGUGGUGAAGAUUGGCCACGCUCACUCAGGCAUGGGCAAGGUCAAAGUGGAAAACCACUACGACUUCCAGGACAUUGCCAGCGUGGUGGCUCUCACCCAGACCUAUGCCACUGCAGAGCCUUUCAUUGACUCCAAGUAUGACAUCCGGGUCCAGAAGAUUGGCAACAACUACAAGGCUUACAUGAGGACAUCGAUCUCAGGGAACUGGAAGACGAACACUGGCUCUGCGAUGCUGGAGCAGAUUGCCAUGUCAGACAGGUACAAACUGUGGGUGGACACCUGCUCUGAGAUGUUUGGCGGCCUGGACAUCUGUGCUGUCAAAGCUGUACAUGGCAAAGAUGGGAAAGACUACAUUUUUGAGGUCAUGGACUGUAGCAUGCCACUGAUUGGGGAACAUCAGGUGGAGGACAGGCAACUCAUCACCGAACUAGUCAUCAGCAAGAUGAACCAGCUGCUGUCCAGGACUCCUGCCCUGUCUCCUCAGAGACCCCUAACAACCCAGCAGCCACAGAGCGGAACACUUAAGGAUCCGGACUCAAGCAAGACCCCACCUCAGCGGCCACCCCCUCAAGGUUGUUUACAGUAUAUUCUCGACUGUAAUGGCAUUGCAGUAGGGCCAAAACAAGUCCAAGCUUCUUAAAAUGAUUGGUGGUUAAUUUUUCAAAGCAGAAAUUUUAAGCCAAAAACAAACGAAAGGAAAGCGGGGAGGGGAAAACAGACCCUCCCACUGGUGCCGUUGCUGCGUUCUUUCAAUGCUGACUGGACUGUGUUUUUCCUAUGCAGUGUCAGCUCCUCUGUCUGGUUGUUUACCUGUUCCUGUUCGUGCUUGUAAUGCUCACUUAUGUUUUCUCUGUAUAACUUGUGAUUCCAGGGCUGUUUGUCAACAGUAUACAAAAGAAUUGUGCCUCUCCCAAGUCCAGUGUGACUUUAUCUUCUGGGUGGUUUGAUAGUGUUUUUAAAAGUAAUAUAUAAUGUGGGGUGAAAUGGGAGUAGGGGGGUGGACAGGGGAGAAACGAAAACCACAAAAAGAAAACCCAACUCCUCUCCUCCCCCCAAGCUCAGUUAAAUCCCCCACCUCCAACUUUCCCUCCACCAGUGUGCUUGGGAUCUUCAAUGAACUGUGCUUUUCGCUUUCUUUCUGCAUGACUAUUGUAACUAGAUAGAACAUUAAGAGAUUUUCAAGAUCAAACUUCCAUAGCUUCAUCCACUGAAUUUGAAGGCAUCCACCUUUUUCUCCAUUUGCUAAAAUUUGGUGCAGUUUGAGUUUAUGUGAAUAGGCUGGCUGUGCCUGUAGAGCUCUUGUGUUUUUAGUGAUGACAUGAAAUACAAAGAACAAGCUAUUUCCAGGAAUGUGUUCUGUAUUUUACAUCCCAGUGUACCCUUUAUUUUAUUAUUAACUAAUUAACUAUGAGAUUUUUAAAAAAUGGGGCCGCUGAUGUGCAAUAUCAAAGUGAACUUGUGAGUAUUUUGUGUGUGUUGAUCUCAGUUGUUUCUUCAUUGUUGCUGUUUCUGGAUCCAGCCAUGUGUGCGCUUGUGUGGACCUGAGGCUGCUUUCUGUUCCCAAAGCUUGACCUGUGUACAGAGAUAAUUCCUUGGCAAUGUUGGACAUAGAAUGCAGGGAGCUACUGAAGGUCUGUCAGGGAUUUGUCCAUUCUGCUCUUGGCCUCUCCUGAGGCCUCAUAAUGGGAGACCAAAUCAAAAAUGUCCCAUGUCACUUGAGUGGGUACACUGCCUACAGAACCUUGAGGUUGACUCCUGCUUCAGUUCUCAGCUGUUUACCACAGCCCUCCAGGGUCCAAAGAUUGAGGAGCUUUCUCUUUCCUGGGAGGAACUGUCUCAGAUUUAGCUUGUGUGUGUUUUGGACAGAGGCUCCACAGCGGUGGCUCUUGAGGAAUCCUCACCAGUUUGUUCUCUUCCCUCUGACAAGCAGCACCUGAGCAGAUGCUGAGGCAGUUCAUUAAACCAGGCCUCAGCUUCAGUGCCUCAUCUUGCCAUCUCCCGGCCAGGCUGGGAACGGGCACCAAGCAGCCGCCUCUAACAAACACCAUGGUCCGUGGAAGUUCAUGCCAGCAGCUUGCCUUUGAGAAGAAAUGCUGCUGGCUCUAUUUUUACAUUCCCUUCCACCUCUAUACUGUCAUGUCACCGUUCUGAACUCCCAGAUCUGAGAAGGAACUAGUGUUGGUGGUAUGUAACAAGAGUUACGUAUCCAGGGGCUUGUGCCUUGGUUUCUCCUUUGAUUGCUGGUAAAUUCUGAGGCCACAGAGAAAUGCAUUGAGUGUGAAUGUUGUCAUCUGUAAUCCCUCCCUCAGCUGAUAAUGGUAGUUGAUCUGUUGUAAAUAUAUACAUAUAUGCAUAUUUGCACUUCCAGAUGGGUUGCAUAAGAAUCAGGUCCUUAAAUACCUCCCAAUCUGAUGAAACGAUAGAAUAAAGUAACAUUUCCCAGAAUGGAGGAAUACAUUAUUUUAUCGUAUAUUUUUGUCCAAGCGAUGAGCUGACGGUGGUAUUGCUUCUCUGCAUGUUAUCAGUGUGUACAUCUGGUGCUUUUCAUGUGUCAUUUGUGAGCCACAAAUGCAAAGUUGCCAUUUGAAUUCAGUCAGGCUACAGGGUGGUGUCAGUCAAGGUCUUUCAGGUGGGGGAGAAAUUGGUUAGGGCUCCCACUGCCAAAUGCAAGCAGAUAGCAUAACCUGACUGUUAUGUGCCCUCAGGCAGCAUGCUUAGGGACAACUCUGUGGCCUGGGGGACAUCUGUGUCACAGUAUAGGAUUGCCAUUCAGGUGUUUUGUACCUAUUUCUUUCCUGACGUUGUCCCCUUUUUUUGUACUGAUCCAACUGGGAGAACCUCAGCCAAUGCUGGAAGUAUGAUUGAAGUACCUCUCUUUUGUGACUCUUGUACAGCUUAAUGUGCAAUAAAGGAAAAGUUAUAUCUGU